GCCCUGGCCUUCGCGCAUCUCCCAGGUUAGCUGCGUGUCCGGGUGCUAGGCUGCAGACCCGCCGCCAUGACGCUGCGCGCGGCCGUCUUCGACCUUGACGGGGUGCUGGCGCUGCCAGCGGUGUUCGGCGUCCUCGGCCGCACGGAGGAGGCCCUGGCGCUGCCCAGAGGACUUCUGAAUGAUGCUUUCCAGAAAGGGGGACCAGAGGGUGCCACUACCCGGCUUAUGAAAGGAGAGAUCACACUUUCCCAGUGGAUACCACUCAUGGAAGAAAACUGCAGGAAGUGCUCCGAGACCGCUAAAGUCUGCCUCCCCAAGAAUUUCUCCAUAAAAGAAAUCUUUGACAAGGCGAUUUCAGCCAGAAAGAUCAACCGCCCCAUGCUCCAGGCAGCUCUCAUGCUCAGGAAGAAAGGAUUCACUACUGCCAUCCUCACCAACACCUGGCUGGACGACCGUGCUGAGAGAGAUGGCCUGGCCCAGCUGAUGUGUGAGCUGAAGAUGCACUUUGACUUCCUGAUAGAGUCGUGUCAGGUGGGAAUGGUCAAACCUGAACCUCAGAUCUACAAGUUUCUGCUGGACACCCUGAAGGCCAGCCCCAGUGAGGUCGUUUUUUUGGAUGACAUCGGGGCUAAUCUGAAGCCAGCCCGUGACUUGGGAAUGGUCACCAUCCUGGUCCAGGACACUGACACGGCCCUGAAAGAACUGGAGAAAGUGACCGGAAUCCAGCUUCUCAAUACCCCGGCCCCUCUGCCGACCUCUUGCAAUCCAAGUGACAUGAGCCAUGGGUACGUGACAGUAAAGCCCAGGGUCCGUCUGCAUUUUGUGGAGCUGGGCUCCGGCCCUGCUGUGUGCCUCUGCCAUGGAUUUCCCGAGAGUUGGUAUUCUUGGAGGUACCAGAUCCCUGCUCUGGCCCAGGCAGGUUACCGGGUCCUAGCUAUGGACAUGAAAGGCUAUGGAGAGUCAUCUGCUCCUCCCGAAAUAGAAGAAUAUUGCAUGGAAGUGUUAUGUAAGGAGAUGGUAACCUUCCUGGAUAAACUGGGCCUCUCUCAAGCAGUGUUCAUUGGCCAUGACUGGGGUGGCAUGCUGGUGUGGUACAUGGCUCUCUUCUACCCCGAGAGAGUGAGGGCGGUGGCCAGUUUGAAUACUCCCUUCAUACCAGCAAAUCCCAACAUGUCCCCUUUGGAGAGUAUCAAAGCCAACCCAGUAUUUGAUUACCAGCUCUACUUCCAAGAACCAGGAGUGGCUGAGGCUGAACUGGAACAGAACCUGAGUCGGACUUUCAAAAGCCUCUUCAGAGCAAGCGAUGAGAGUGUUUUAUCCAUGCAUAAAGUCUGUGAAGCGGGAGGACUUUUUGUAAAUAGCCCAGAAGAGCCCAGCCUCAGCAGGAUGGUCACUGAGGAGGAAAUCCAGUUCUAUGUGCAGCAGUUCAAGAAGUCUGGUUUCAGAGGUCCUCUAAACUGGUACCGAAACAUGGAAAGGAACUGGAAGUGGGCUUGCAAAAGCUUGGGACGGAAGAUCCUGAUUCCGGCCCUGAUGGUCACGGCGGAGAAGGACUUCGUGCUCGUUCCUCAGAUGUCCCAGCACAUGGAGGACUGGAUUCCCCACCUGAAAAGGGGACACAUUGAGGACUGUGGGCACUGGACACAGAUGGACAAGCCAACCGAGGUGAAUCAGAUCCUCAUUAAGUGGCUGGAUUCUGAUGCCCGGAACCCACCGGUGGUCUCAAAGAUGUAGAACGCAGCGUGUGCCCACGCUCAGCAGGUGUGCCAUCCUUCCACCUGCUGGGGCACCAUUCUUAGUAUACAGAGGUGGCCUUACACACAUCUUGCAUGGAUGGCAGCAUUGUUCUGAAGGGGUUUGCAGAAAAAAAAGAUUUUCUUUACAUAAAGUGAAUCAAAUUUGACAUUAUUUUAGAUCCCAGAGAAAUCAGGUGUGAUUAGUUCUCCAGGCAUGAAUGCAUCGUCCCUUUAUCUGUAAGAACCCUUAGUGUCCUGUAGGGGGACAGAAUGGGGUGGCCAGGUGGUGAUUUCUCUUUGACCAAUGCAUAGUUUGGCAGAAAAAUCAGCCGUUCAUUUAGAAGAAUCUUAGCAGAGAUUGGGAUGCCUUACUCAAUAAAGCUAAGAUGACUAUGCUGCUGGCUGUCUUUGUUCUUGGAGAGGUGGAGUGACUGUUCACGGAGAAUGCACGGCAUGGGGAUGAACCCUUUCCCUCUGCUUUUGAGCCCUGUUCUGGGCUCCAAGGUGCUGUAUGAUCUAGGCCGUGCUGGCCAGGAGACAAUCCUAUGGGGAUGGCAGUGGUGUCUUGUGCUCUGUCCCCUAGAGCAGUCACUGGCCACAGGUAGCCACCUGCCUUUCUCCCGGCUUCCCUAGCAGAGUUUGCUCAGGCACAAAUGUGCACCUGGAGCAUUUGAAAUGUGCUAGUGAGGCUGAGGAAGAGAAUUUUAAAUUUCAUUGAAUUGUAAUCAGUUUAAAGUUAAAUAGCAGCAGCUGCCAUGAGGCUCAGGCAGAUCCAGCUCAUCUUCCCCUCUGCCCCCUCCUCCCUAUCUUCCCCUCUACCCUCUCCUGCCUCCUGUCACAUCCGGUUAGGCUCCCAUCUCACUGAUGUGUCUCCUGCAGUGGUCUCUCCCCUGCCCUGCUUCCAGCCCCAGAGUCCUGGAGCAGCAGCCUCCUCACGGGUCUUGCCGCCCACAUGGUUGGAUCCUGAAACUCGCAGGGCCUCCCCCAACUGCCCCUGCCCACCCCCAGCCCGGCCCCAUCACCCUCCAAUUCCUAACCGC